GGGGCUUCUCGGCCCGAGGCAGAGGAACAGGGAAGAUGGCGGCUGUGGUGGAGAAUGUAGUGAAGCUGUGAGUGGUCGUUUCUUUCUCUCCUAGGGCGGCAGGUUUUGUAAAGGGCCUGGGAGUAGGGGGCGGUGGGGGAAGGGACUAGGCGGAGAGAGGGACAUCCCCGGGAAAGCCAUGUUGCGACUCCUGGUGGGGAGGGCAACAGGAGACUCCGGAGAAGACGUUGCGCUUCUUUGGAAACUUGUGGAGGCCCUGGUGGGGGCACACUGGAGCCCCGACGGGCGGCAUCCCUGCGGGGCUGUGUGGCCUCAGCGUUCCUCGGGGCUGACGGUUUCCAGAGCAUGGCGCCCUGCCUGCACGCGAGACUCACCGUCCCGGUCCUCUCCCGAGACGCCUCAGUCCGGAGGAGCGGGGCCGAGGCCCGGGCGGCCCUACGGCUGGCCCGCCGCCCACCCCGCCCCGUCCCGUCCCGUUCGCUGCAGCAACAGGCUCGGCGGCCCCUGCGGAGUGCACUGCGGGGCUGGCUGUUUCAGUUCCAGGCAGCCCCGUGAUGUUUGGGAGGAUCUUGGGUGGCAGGUACCUAAGACUACAAAUAUUCUUGGGAAGAAUUUAUCGAGGAGCGGAUCCAGAAGGGAAGGAACUUCAGGGGAGUGGGCCUUGGCCCCGUCCAGUAGCAGCCAUCAAAAACCUGCAACUGGACCGAAGCCGUUCAGGACAGCUUAGCCUAAAGGGGCAUCUAGCCUUGGGGAGCAGUACUACAAAGAUGCCAUGGAGCAGUGCCACAAUUACAAUGCUCGCCUCUGUGCUGAGCGCAGCGUGCGCCUGCCUUUCUUGGACUCACAGACCGGAGUAGCCCAGAGCAAUUGUUACAUCUGGAUGGAAAAGCGACACCGGGGUCCAGGAUUGGCCUCCGGACAGCUGUACUCCUACCCUGCCCGGCGCUGGCGGAAAAAGCGGCGAGCCCAUCCCCCUGAGGAUCCACGACUUUCCUUCCCAUCUAUUAAGCCAGACACAGACCAGACCCUGAAGAAGGAGGGGCUGAUCUCUCAGGAUGGCAGUAGUUUAGAGGCUCUGUUGCGCACUGACCCCCUGGAGAAGCGAGGUGCCCCGGAUCCCCGAGUUGAUGAUGACAGCCUGGGCGAGUUUCCUGUGACCAACAGUCGAGCGCGAAAGCGGAUCCUAGAACCAGAUGACUUCCUGGAUGACCUCGAUGAUGAAGACUAUGAAGAAGAUACUCCCAAGCGUCGGGGAAAGGGGAAAUCCAAGGGUAAGGGUGUGGGCAGUGCCCGUAAGAAGCUGGAUGCUUCCAUCCUGGAGGACCGGGAUAAGCCCUAUGCCUGUGACAAUAGUUUCAAACAAAAGCAUACCUCGAAAGCGCCCCAGAGAGUUUGUGGAAAACGUUACAAGAACCGACCAGGCCUCAGUUACCACUAUGCCCACUCCCACUUGGCUGAGGAGGAGGGCGAGGACAAGGAAGACUCUCAACCACCCACUCCUGUUUCCCAGAGGUCUGAGGAGCAGAAAUCCAAAAAGGGUCCUGAUGGAUUGGCCUUGCCCAACAACUACUGUGACUUCUGCCUGGGGGACUCAAAGAUUAACAAGAAGACGGGACAACCCGAGGAGCUGGUGUCCUGUUCUGACUGUGGCCGCUCAGGGCAUCCAUCUUGCCUCCAAUUUACCCCCGUGAUGAUGGCGGCAGUGAAGACAUACCGCUGGCAGUGCAUCGAGUGCAAAUGUUGCAAUAUCUGCGGCACCUCCGAGAAUGACGACCAGUUGCUCUUCUGUGAUGACUGCGAUCGUGGCUACCACAUGUACUGUCUCACCCCGUCCAUGUCUGAGCCCCCUGAAGGAAGUUGGAGCUGCCACCUGUGUCUGGACCUGUUGAAAGAGAAAGCUUCCAUCUACCAGAACCAGAACUCCUCUUGAUGUGGCCACCCACCUGCUCCCCGACAUAUCUAAGGCUGUUUCUCUCCUCCACUUCAUAUUUCAUACCCAUCUUUCCCUUCUUCCUCCUCUCCUUCACAAAUCCAGAGAACCUUGGGGUGGUUGUGCCAGCCUGCCUUUGGCAGCUGCAAGCUGAGGUGGCAGCUCUGACCACCUCUGGCCCCAGGCCCUCAGGGAGAAAGGAGCAACACACUGCCCCUAGGCGUGCGUGUGGCCCAGUUUCUCUCUGCUCUCCAUUAAGUGCAUUCACUCUGCUUGCCUUGGGCCCAGCCCCUGGUGAUCACAGGGUUCAAACAGUGUCCUCCUAGAAAGAGUGGGAGAGCAGCUCACUUCUCUGUGUUCUGCCUCCCCUCUGGUCUCCAGAGUUUUCCUGUCCUCUAGAGGCAAGCCAGGCCAGGGAGCUGGGAGCGAGCAAGCUGAGGCCACGUCCACAAGGAGCUUUUCAUGCCCCUGUGCCGCAUAGCCUCACCUCUUUCCUCCAGAGUGGCUCUCUGCGGCCCUGUGUUCCUGCUACAGAGUGUUCUUUUCUGGAGUCAGGAUGUUCUCGGUCACCCUCCUGGUUCUGCCCUGUCCCAUUCCACCCCACCCCAGGGGGAACAGUAGCUUCACCUUGUUAUUCCCAUUGCUCUCCUGGCUCACUCUUACGGUCGGUCUCCAGUGACUGAAGCAUUCCCCACCCUUGGAAUUUCUCAUCUUCUGCCUCCCUUCCUACUCCUUUUGGUUUUGUGGGGAGAGGGGAAGGAUCAGGGGGCCAGGCCAGCAGCUCGGGGGCCACAAGGAGAUGGAUAAUGUGCCUGUUUUUUAACACAACAAAAAAGCCUACCUCCAAAAUCCCCUUUUUGUUCUUCCUGGACCUGGGCAUUCAGCCUCCUGCUCUUAACUGAAUUGGGAGCCUCUGCCACCUGCCCCGUGUAUCCUGGCUCUCAGCUCAUGGGGAAGCCACAUAGACAUCCCUUUCUUCCCUUGCACGCUCGCUAGCAGCUGGUAAGGUCUUCACACCCUGAUUCCUCAAGUUUUCUGCUUAGUGGCACUGACAUUAAGUAGUGGGGGGACAGUCCAUGCCAGGACACCCUGGAGUAGCCUUCCCCCUUGGCCGUGGGCAGGCCCUAACUCACUGUCGCUUUGGAGUUGAGGUGUCUUUUUUUUUUCUUUCUUUAGUUCCUGUAUUCUAAACAUUAGUAAAAAUAAAUGUUUUUACACAGAGCCCUCUGCUGGAUGGUUUAUCUCCUGCCUUUCUCCAUUAAGAAGGCCAUUUCAUCCUAAGAUUUCCAUGAUGGUGGUUUUUUUUUUUAAUGUUUUGAAAUACAGCUUUUUUCCCCCCAAAUUAAAAUUUUUUUGUGGAACCCCAAUAUGUAAAGCGAAUAUAAAAUUGGUUAUUUUGUUUUGUUACAUAAAUUCAAGUUUAUAACAAUUCUUUGUUAUAAAGAACAAUGAAGCUGUUUUGAUCAAUACAAAAUUUGGGUUAAAAUCAACUUUAACAUCUAUUUUUAUGUUUCAGUUGAUUUGGAGAAUUCUCCUAGUCUUGGAUACAUAGAUGGAAGUGAUGACAGGUUUAUAACAGUUGACCUUGCAAUCUCAGACAUUUAAAACAGGACCAGAAGUUUAUAUAAAUAUAAUUAAUAAGCAAACUAAUGACAUCACCAUGGGACACACACAAAAGUUCUUGCAGGAGCAGGGUCUGUGUGGCUUCAGUUGCCUGCAGCGCUCCCAGGCCAGAGCAAGUGCUCUAGGAUCUGAACUGCCCGCAGUGCAGCCCUGCAGCCUUUCCCAGGGCACGUUGAUGUGCACACAGUUUCCCUGAAGGCAAAGUGAACAUGUGGAGAGCUUACGUGGCAGCGCGUAUGUCUUCAGUGUGUGUUUUAGAAGUCCAACUGUUGUUUUUAUGUUUUUAAAGGAAAGAUUUGAAUCAAGCAGUUAUGGGCCCCCUGAAGUAUCCUUUUUUCUAGAACAUUCUGAAAGUCAUCCUUGCCUAUGGGAAGCCUAGGCCGGCCUGCACUGUUAUGUUCAAUAAAUAAGCAGGGUGCUCUGGGCUGGGGAUUGUGUGAGGAGCAGAGCGCAGCCCGUCCUCAUGCUUUUCCACUGAAGUAGGCCAGGCAGAGAGGGAGUACAGCAAUGGAUGCGCUUUGGCAGCUGAGUAGUCCGAGAGCCAGAAAAGAAAUGUGGAAAAUAAGAACGCUGUAGCAGGCCUAGGUGAGGAAAUUUAGGAAGGGUUUGCGGGAGGUAGGAUUUGAGAUGGGUCUUGGAGAGUUGGACAGUGUCAGCCGGUAGGACGGGGGUGCGGACGGAAGCCUGUGAGGAAGGCAGAGGAUGCGGAGCUGUGAGCGGAGGGAGCAGCGAGGCUGGAGAGCAGCUGGGCUGCGGGUCAAGACGUCUGCGUUUAAUUCGGGACUGAAGGUUAGCAGGGAAGGGAACGAUGCCAGAUCUUGAGUUUAAGAACUUGAAUCUUGUAAAGUACCAAAUCUAAUAAAAUACUCGUCCUAAAUCA